ACCAGGCAUAGGACAUUUUCCUUUAAUCCUAAUAAAAACACUGGGAGAUAGACACUGCUCACUCACUUACAGAGAAGAAAACAGGCUUAGAGAGGCUAAAUCAGAUGUCUUAGGUCACAUAGCUACGAUAUGACAAAACAAAUAUUUGAAUCCAAAGUCUUCUCACCCAGAGGCUUUCAGCAGGGAACUAACAUGAUCCACCAGGACUGGGGGAGUACAAGACAACCUCUGCCCUGGGGGAGUUUAUUGCCUAGUCAGGCAGAUAAGAGGGAAACAUAAGUAAUGCAAGAGAGUGACCGGCAGAAAUUGGCCUGGGAGUGGGGUUUUAUGGAGGGAGAGAUGAGAGAUGAGCUGGGCUGCAGGAGCUUGGCAGGGGGAUCUGCAGGCCCAGGGAACCCCAAGCAACUUUAGGAGGUAGGAAGGGCCCAAGGCAGGGGCUUGUGGCCUUGAAGUUGUCUGCCUCCCACCCCAACACCUCUGGAGGGAGGUGUCUGCCAUUAUCAUGAGGAAUGGAUUGCCCAGCAUCUGCUGCUGAUGUUACCAGAAAGGGGUCUGGAUCCAGACCCCAAGAGAGGGCUCUUGGAUCUCGUGCAAGAAAGAAUUCAGUGUGAGUCUGUAAAGUGAAAGCAAGUUUAUUAGGAAAGUAAAGGAAUAAAAGAAUGGCUACUCCAUAGGCAGAGCAGCCCCGAGGGCUGCUUAUUGCCCAUUUUUAUGGUUAUUUCAUGAUGAUAUGCUAAACAAGGGGUGGAUUAUUCAUGCCUCCCUUUUAGACCAUAUAGGGUAACUUCCUGACAUUGCCAUGGCAUUUGUAAACUGUCAUGGUGCUGGUGGGAGUGUAGCAGUGAGGACAACCAGAGGGCAUUCUCAUCGCCAUCUUGGCAUUGGUGGGAUUUAGCCGGCUUCUUUACUGCAAGCUGUUUUAUCAGCAAGGUCAUUAUGAUCUGUACCCUGUGCUGACCUCCUAUCUCAUUCUGUGACCUGGAAUGCCUAACUCUUUGGGAAUGCAGCUCAGUAGGUCUCAACCUUAUUUUACCCAAUCCCUACUCAAGAUGAAGAUGGAGAUGGAGAUGGGGCCAGCGGGUGAGGUACCCCAGGUACCAGACAAGGAAACCAAAGCCACAAUGGGCACAGAAAACACACCUGGAGGCAAAGCCAGCCCAGACCCUCAGGACGUGCGGCCAAGUGUGUUCCAUAACAUCAAGCUGUUCGUUCUGUGCCACAGCCUGCUGCAGCUGGCGCAGCUCAUGAUCUCCGGCUACCUAAAGAGCUCCAUCUCCACAGUGGAGAAGCGCUUCGGCCUCUCCAGCCAGACGUCGGGGCUGCUGGCCUCCUUCAACGAGGUGGGGAACACAGCCUUGAUUGUGUUUGUGAGCUAUUUUGGCAGCCGGGUGCACCGACCCCGAAUGAUUGGCUAUGGGGCUAUCCUUGUGGCCCUGGCGGGCCUGCUCAUGACUCUCCCGCACUUCAUCUCGGAGCCAUACCGCUACGACAACACCAGCCCUGAGGAUAUGCCACAGGACUUCAAGGCUUCCCUGUGCCUGCCCACAACCUCGGCCCCAGCCUCGGCCCCCUCCAAUGGCAACUGCUCAAGCUACACAGAAACCCAGCAUCUGAGUGUGGUGGGGAUCAUGUUCGUGGCACAGACCCUGCUGGGCGUGGGCGGGGUGCCCAUUCAGCCCUUUGGCAUCUCCUACAUCGAUGACUUUGCCCACAACAGCAACUCGCCCCUCUACCUCGGGAUCCUGUUUGCAGUGACCAUGAUGGGGCCAGGCCUGGCCUUUGGGCUGGGCAGCCUCAUGCUGCGCCUUUAUGUGGACAUUAACCAGAUGCCAGAAGGUGGUAUCAGCCUGACCAUAAAGGACCCCCGAUGGGUGGGUGCCUGGUGGCUGGGUUUCCUCAUCGCUGCCGGUGCAGUGGCCCUGGCUGCCAUCCCCUACUUCUUCUUCCCCAAGGAAAUGCCCAAGGAAAAACGUGAGCUUCAGUUUCGGCGAAAGGUCUUAGCAGUCACAGACUCACCUGCCAGGAAGGGCAAGGACUCUCCCUCUAAGCAGAGCCCUGGGGAGUCCACGAAGAAGCAGGAUGGCCUAGUCCAGAUUGCACCAAACCUGACUGUGAUCCAGUUCAUUAAAGUCUUCCCCAGGGUGCUGCUGCAGACCCUACGCCACCCCAUCUUCCUGCUGGUGGUCCUGUCCCAGGUAUGCUUGUCAUCCAUGGCUGCGGGCAUGGCCACCUUCCUGCCCAAGUUCCUGGAGCGCCAGUUUUCCAUCACAGCCUCCUACGCCAACCUGCUCAUCGGCUGCCUCUCCUUCCCUUCGGUCAUCGUGGGCAUCGUGGUGGGUGGCGUCCUGGUCAAGCGGCUCCACCUGGGCCCUGUGGGAUGCGGUGCCCUUUGCCUGCUGGGGAUGCUGCUGUGCCUCUUCUUCAGCCUGCCGCUCUUCUUUAUCGGCUGCUCCAGCCACCAGAUUGCGGGCAUCACACACCAGACCAGUGCCCACCCUGGGCUGGAGCUGUCUCCAAGCUGCAUGGAGGCCUGCUCCUGCCCAUUGGACGGCUUUAACCCUGUCUGCGACCCCAGCACUCGUGUGGAAUACAUCACACCCUGCCACGCAGGCUGCUCAAGCUGGGUGGUCCAGGAUGCUCUGGACAACAGCCAGGUUUUCUACACCAACUGCAGCUGCGUGGUGGAGGGCAACCCCGUGCUGGCAGGAUCCUGCGACUCAACGUGCAGCCAUCUGGUGGUGCCCUUCCUGCUCCUGGUCAGCCUGGGCUCGGCCCUGGCCUGUCUCACCCACACACCCUCCUUCAUGCUCAUCCUAAGAGGAGUGAAGAAAGAAGACAAGACUUUGGCUGUGGGCAUCCAGUUCAUGUUCCUGAGGAUUUUGGCCUGGAUGCCCAGCCCCGUGAUCCACGGCAGCGCCAUCGACACCACCUGUGUGCACUGGGCCCUGAGCUGUGGGCGUCGAGCUGUCUGUCGCUACUACAAUAAUGACCUGCUCCGAAACCGGUUCAUCGGCCUCCAGUUCUUCUUCAAAACAGGUUCUGUGAUCUGCUUCGCCUUAGUUUUGGCUGUCCUGAGGCAGCAGGACAAAGAGGCAAGGACCAAAGAGAGCAGAUCCAGCCCUGCCGUAGAGCAGCAAUUGCUAGUGUCGGGGCCAGGGAAGAAGCCAGAGGAUUCCCGAGUGUGAGCUGUCUUGGGGCCCCACCUGGCCAAGAGUAGCAGCCACAGCAGUACCUCCUCUGAGUCCUUUGCCCAAGAUUGGGUGUCAAGAGCCCUGUGUUCCAUUCUGGCUCCUCCACUAAAUUGCUGUGUGACUUCAGGCAAGACAUUGAUCCUCUCUCAGCCUUUGCUUGCUAGUCUGAACCAAAGAGUUGUUUGGGCAUUUGCUGUGUUGGCCAUUUCUGGAGCAAGAGGGUCUUCUUCCUCCUUCCCCCAGCCAGCCAGCUGUCCUGGGGCCAGGCUUUCCUGGGUGGAAAGAAGUAUACCUUUCCCUGGGGCCCUAGGAUAGCAAAGUGAGCCAUAGUGGGCCAGGCUGCCCUCCAUGCUGGGCCCCAGCCCAGGUCUGCACUCGCCUGGAUCACCUUCUUUGAGCCUUAGCCAUCUCCUGUCAGGUAGGAAUGAACUUGCCAGCCUUCAGGCUCGUUCAGCUAUGACCAUCUGUGCGGUCAGGGUACACUCAGCUCUCCUCCCCAACUCCAGCAGCCUUUAAGAAGUGUCCCUUUGGCGCCCCCUGGAGGCAGAGCACUGAGCUGGACCCUGGGUAGACUCCCACAGGGAGGACGGAGCUGGCCUCAGGAGUGGGACACCCAGACUUGGCAGGGCCUUCAAGAGGCCUGUGUGGGGGCCCCAGGAAUCCUUAGCUGAAGCGGGGAGACUCACUCUCCAUCUCAGGAAAUUCUAGCCCUUGCCCUCAGGGAGCCACGGUUGAGGGUGAGGCCCAACACCUGCCUUAGGGCCCUGGGUGGGCAAGUCUGGGCCCUGGGGUAGGGAGGGAGACUCAGGCCCACACUUGGGUAUUUUCUAAUUUCAGACAAACACACACUCAGCGCGCACUCACUGAUUCCUACACAUUGCCAAGAUUUCACACAUGUGACCAGGGGCCACCAAAGUCCCUGUGACCUUUGUGACUAGGAUCCUAAUUUCUCUAUUUUCUCCUGGGUGCCUGGGUCUGUGUCACCUGGGGCAGUGUGGAUAAUGUUUAGUUCUGUGACACUGUUUUUUGGGGGUGGCACCUGGUUCUCCGAUGCCUGGGCUGGUGUCAGGCCCAGGACUGUAGUGCUGGGAGCAGUAAAGCUCAGCUCUGUGUAAUGAGUGAUGCUAUGGCUUGCUCGUGUCUUAUGAUCCAAUCCUUUUCUACAUCAGCCCUUGUUUUGUUUUAUGGCUAGUCUUAUCUGGCCUGGUUAUUUCCUUGCGGGGAGGAGAGGGUUUGCUAAUCUGCUCCCAGCCCAACCUAUUACCACCCCACCUCGCUGGGACCUACUGCUCGGGAGGCAGCAGACAGGGAGCCACCAGCAGUGGCUUCCUGGCCCUGUGCUGGGGGUGGGGGGAAGCUGGGGGCACAUGUGGCCCUUGCCUUCUGAGCAGCUCCCAGUGCCAGGGCUUUGAGACUUUCCCACAUGAUAAAAGAAAAGGGAGGUACAGAAGUUCCAAUUCCCUUUUUAUUUUGCUGGUUGGUAUCUGUAAAUGUUUAAUAAAUAUCUGAGCAUGUAUCUAUCAACGCCAAGAAUUUCAAAGUCUCCUUCAACAAUAUGAGGCUUUUAGGAUGUUUAUAUUCCUUCAUCCCUCUUGUUUCCCAGGUUUUGCAGGGAAAAAAAGUCUGGAAUUAUAGAUACAGCUUAUUAUUAAAUUUGUUCUUGCAUAAUGUCUCUUCUAUUACAAAAAUUCUUUCUUCAUAAACUGCAUUAGAGGUUUGCAACAACCACAUCAUUUCCAUUAACUUAGAUUUAGGUUUUACUGGAUUCAUUGCUCACCAUUAUUGCUUGUAUAUUACAUCUUUUCCAAUCUUUAUAUUCUGGUCUAAUUUUUGUUUGAGUGUCUUCGUCUACUAAUGGUUUCAAAAAUGGAAUAAGGUCAUGAGGAUUUCUGAAUCCUCACCUGUCCAAAUUGUCAUUCACAUUUUAUAGAAGAGGAAACUGGCUCAGAAAGCACAAGUGACU